GAGCGCAGAGCCAGCGAGCCAGCGAGCGAGCGAGCGGGAGCCGGAGCCUCGCGCCCCCCGCUCCACUCCGAUUCUCUCCGCGCCAGAGCCAGCGCGCCAGGUAGGGUGAGCCGGUGGUGGUGGUGCCGCUGCCGCUGCCGACCUUUUUGGCCCUUACCUCACGUCCCAGGGUCCUGCGGGCCCUCAAGUUGUGGGGCGCCCGCGCUGCUGUGUCCAGACAGCGUUCCCUGAGAGCUCCGGGAAGCGGGAAGACAGCCCCGGGCGUCCCGCCUUUCUUCUCCAGAAAACGCACGCCCCACAUCGCACUCCCCCGUUCCUCCUGCUCCAGCGUCCUCUGGUCCUUCUUUCUGUCUGUGCCUCCGUCUUUGUCUCAACCUCUCAGGCUUGCUCGCUCCCUGCCCAGAUUUUGUGGCCCAGGCUCCUGGCUGUCUGACUCCGGGUUUCUGUCCCCUUCCUGCCUCUGAGCUUCCGUCUGGGCCUCCCCUCUGGGAGACUUGCGACUUGACCAGUUUUGGCUUCAGCCCCCAUCUGGGUCCCUGUCUCCAUCUGUGCUGGUCUUCCUCCCUGCUUCUCCCUCGCUUGCCUGGGUAAGCUGCUGCUUUCCUGAUCCCCAGAGGAGCCCAGUGCCCCUGCCCUGGGGAGCUGAGGGGGCAAAAUGAAGAGGCUCAGCCUCCGUGGCCAGCACAUGGGGUCCUUGAGUUAGUUGCUGCCCUUCUUCAAACUCAGUUUCCUUUCCUGUUCUGAGGAAAGAGGUAUGUCCCUCUCCCAGCCUUUCCAAGCCUGUGUGAUUGUGAGAGCCUUUGUGGGGUGUGUGUUUGGGAAGGCAACUGGGGUACAAAUGAUUGGACGCAGUGGGGAAGAGACAGGGAGGGGGUCUCUGAGGGCCAUGGCUAGGGUGGGCAGGGCCCUGAAGCUGAGGAUGGGGAGAUUGGAAAUGGUGACUUUCUCUGCUGGGUCGGGAGUGAAGAGAAAACAGAGGCACAAAAUCUCAAGCAGUGUUCUACACAGAGCUAGAGAGUCCCGCACUCUCACCCUCAGCACUGUUUGGAGACUCUAGCCCCCAACCCUGACACACACAUACGUGAACAUCUGCUUGCCCUGUUGACUUAGGACCUUGAGCCACUUGGGUACCCUCCCUGAGGCCAGCCAUUCCACCUUGCUGUCUCAUUCCCAGGGCUUAGUGUCUCUAUUCCUUCCUCAGUCAGCAAACUGUGGGGAUGGCUUUUUAAGAACCAAAGGUUAGAACCCUUGGGUGUUCACAUGGGCUCCAGUCUCCCCACGGGUUGGAGACUGUCCCUUAGAGAUGCUUCCCUUCCUCUUCCCUGGUGGGUCCUGAGACAGCAGUUCCUUCUCUCUGGAAAUCCAAGGCUCAGGAUGGGGACCUCUGAGUUUGUGACUGUGACAUAGUCUGUUCCAAAGGUAUUGACCUCGGGGUCCUGGGAGGUUUGUGCUGUUCUUGGACACCCUUUGAAUUACAGAGGGGUCAGCAUUGGCUGGGGUCUCCUGUCCUCUGCCUGGGACUUCACUGCUUGCAUCUCUCCCCACUGCUGAGUUUGGUAGGGGAAUAUGGCCCAUCUCUCACCAAGCUGAGGCCAGGGCUGAGAGACAGGUCCAGGGGAGUCCCAGGAGCUUCUCAACCUACUUAAUGACACCAUCCUGUCCCUCCCUGGCUUUUGAGUACCUAGGAAAGGGGCUCGUGGGGAGGCAGAGUCAGAAGGGGCAGCUGCUCUCAGGUUCCACUUUUCCUGGUCUGUUUUUCUGUCUUUCUAUCUCUCUGCAGGAGCUGGGUCCCUUCGCAUCUCUCUUCUUGUCUGUCCUUUCCUGGUCCCUGUUUCCUCCUCUCUUUGCCUUCGCUGCUUCUAAUCUCAUCCCCUGGAGACCCAGGUCUGCGGGACCCAUCCAUCCCCUUUGGGGCCAUGGGAUCGCUGCUUGCGCUCCUGGCACUGCUGCUGCUGUGGGGUGCUGUGGCUGAGGGCCCAGCCAAGAAGGUGCUGACCCUGGAGGGAGACUUGGUGCUGGGUGGGCUGUUCCCAGUGCACCAGAAGGGCGGCCCAGCAGAGGACUGUGGUCCUGUCAAUGAGCACCGUGGCAUCCAGCGCCUGGAGGCCAUGCUUUUUGCACUGGACCGCAUCAACCGUGACCCGCACCUGCUGCCUGGCGUGCGCCUGGGUGCACACAUCCUCGACAGUUGCUCCAAGGACACACAUGCGCUGGAGCAGGCACUGGACUUUGUGCGUGCCUCACUCAGCCGUGGUGCUGAUGGCUCACGCCACAUCUGCCCCGACGGCUCUUAUGCGACCCAUGGUGAUGCUCCCACUGCCAUCACUGGUGUUAUUGGCGGUUCCUACAGUGAUGUCUCCAUCCAGGUGGCCAACCUCUUGAGGCUAUUUCAGAUCCCACAGAUUAGCUACGCCUCUACCAGUGCCAAGCUGAGUGACAAGUCCCGCUAUGACUACUUUGCCCGCACAGUGCCUCCUGACUUCUUCCAAGCCAAGGCCAUGGCUGAGAUUCUCCGCUUCUUCAACUGGACCUAUGUGUCCACUGUGGCGUCUGAGGGCGACUAUGGCGAGACAGGCAUUGAGGCCUUUGAGCUAGAGGCUCGUGCCCGCAACAUCUGUGUGGCCACCUCGGAGAAAGUGGGCCGUGCCAUGAGCCGCGCGGCCUUUGAGGGUGUGGUGCGAGCCCUGCUGCAGAAGCCCAGUGCCCGCGUGGCUGUCCUGUUCACCCGUUCUGAGGAUGCCCGGGAGCUGCUUGCUGCCAGCCAGCGCCUCAAUGCCAGCUUCACCUGGGUGGCCAGUGAUGGUUGGGGGGCCCUGGAGAGUGUGGUGGCAGGCAGUGAGGGGGCUGCUGAGGGUGCUAUCACCAUCGAGCUGGCCUCCUACCCCAUCAGUGACUUUGCCUCCUACUUCCAGAGCCUGGACCCUUGGAACAACAGCCGGAACCCCUGGUUCCGUGAAUUCUGGGAGCAGAGGUUCCGCUGCAGCUUCCGGCAGCGAGACUGCGCAGCCCACUCUCUCCGGGCUGUGCCCUUUGAGCAGGAGUCCAAGAUCAUGUUUGUGGUCAAUGCAGUGUACGCCAUGGCCCAUGCGCUCCACAACAUGCACCGUGCCCUCUGCCCCAACACCACCCGGCUCUGUGACGCGAUGCGGCCAGUUAACGGGCGCCGCCUCUACAAGGACUUUGUGCUCAACGUCAAGUUUGAUGGUGACCUGAAAGUCUCCUGAAAUCAAAAGUUAUUUUAAUAAGAGUGCCAGCUUUAAGAGAAAUGACUGCUGCAGAUCAUCACUAUGCUUCAGGAAGAAUCACCGUGGGAACAGUGGGAGACAAAGCUUGGAAGCCCUGGCCCAGGGUUAAGAUGAAGAGUACUUCCAAUAGAACUGACAUUCAGAGUUAGCUACAAUCAGUGUAGGGGUUAGGGUUGGAAUCUGGGGUCCGAUUUGGUUGAUGUUAGAGCAAGGCUAAAUUCAGCAUGUUUGGCUUGGGUGGAAUUUAUGGUAGGGCUAGAGUUGGAUUUUGAGAACUUUUAGGCUGAGUAGAAAGAGUAGGUGCUUGAGGGGACCUGGGUUUGAAUCUAGGCUGCACUAUUCACUCAUGGGGCCUUAAGCAUGUCUUCUGCUUUCUUGAACCCUGAUUUCUCACUGGGGCCAGGGAUGGCUGUAAAUCCUGGCUAGAGCCUGGCUGGGAGAUGUGAGGUUUACAGGGGAUGAAGUGGGGGUGGAGAGAGGAAGUGAUUUUCCAGCCACUGACCACAUUCUGGUGAAUGGCAGUGGUUGCAGGUGACCAGUGAGGUUGGGAUUCAGUUUGCACCAGGAUGACUGUUAGGACUAGGGGUGCUGGAGCUGGGGUUGUUGUUAGGAUUAGUGGGGACAGGAUUGGAGCUGAGACUGGGUUUAGCCUUAGCAUUGAGUUUGGGGAGAGGGCUGUAGUGUAUGUUUCGAUGAAGUUGGGAUUUGGAGCCUGGGUUGGAAAGUGUUGGAUAGUACUAAAGUUGAAUUUGGGGAGUCAUGGUUGGGGAUUGAUGUGGGCAUUAGGUUUUUGGAGAUGUCUGGGCUUUAAGGCUGGGAUUACAUUUGGCAUUUAGGGUUGGGGUUUGAUGUUGGAGUUUAGGAGUAAGACUUUGUUGUCAUCUCUCAUUUAGAAAAAUGAUUGGGGUCAAGGCAGGAUUUAGUAUUGGGUUAAGGAUUGGAAGGGCUAAUGGUGGUCUUAGCUCUGGCAUUUGGGUUCCAUGUUAGGGUGAAUGUUGAGGUCACAUCAGGGUAACACACUAGUCCAACCUUCUCUUCCUUCCCUCCCCCAUCCUAGCCCCCUUUCGCCCAGCUGACACCCACAAUGAGGUCCGCUUUGACCGCUUUGGUGAUGGUAUUGGCCGCUACAACAUCUUCACCUAUCUGCGUGCAGGCAGUGGGCGCUAUCGCUACCAGAAGGUGGGCUACUGGGCAGAAGGCUUGACUCUGGACACCAGCCUCAUCCCAUGGGCCUCACCCUCAGCCGGCCCCCUGCCCGCCUCUC